GCUCUUGCUGCGACGCAGCGGUCGGAAGCGGAGCAAGGUCGAGGCCGGGUUGGCGCCGGAGCCGGGGCCGCUUGGAGCUCGUGUGGGGUCUCCGGUCCAGGGCGCGGCAUGGGCGUCCUGGCCGCAGCGGCGCGCUGCCUGGUCCGGGGUGCGGACCGAAUGAGCAAGUGGACGAGCAAGCGGGGCCCGCGCAGCUUCAGGGGCCGCAAGGGCCGGGGCGCCAAGGGCAUCGGCUUCCUCACCUCGGGCUGGAGGUUCGUGCAGAUCAAGGAGAUGGUCCCGGAGUUCGUCGUCCCGGAUCUGACCGGCUUCAAGCUCAAGCCCUACGUGAGCUACCUCGCCCCUGAGAGCGAGGAGACGCCCCUGACGGCCGCGCAGCUCUUCAGCGAAGCCGUGGCGCCUGCCAUCGAAAAGGACUUCAAGGACGGUACCUUCGACCCUGACAACCUGGAAAAGUACGGCUUCGAGCCCACACAGGAGGGAAAGCUCUUCCAGCUCUACCCCAGGAACUUCCUGCGCUAGCUGGGCGGGGGAGGGGCGGCCUGCCCUCAUCUCAUUUCUAUUAAACGCCUUUGCCAGCUA